GCUAAGCAAAGGCAGUGAGUGUUUGGAAAUGAGGAAAUAAUAAAGGAAAGAGCACACGAAUGCCCCAUGGAAAAUUACAAUCAAACAUCAACUGAUUUCAUCUUAUUAGGAUUCUUCCCACCAUCAAGAAUUGGCCUUUUCCUCUUCAUCCUCAUUGUUUUCAUUUUCCUAAUGGCUCUAAUUGGAAACCUAUCCAUGAUUCUUCUCAUCUUCUUGGACACCCAUCUCCACACACCCAUGUAUUUCCUACUUAGUCAGCUCUCCCUCAUUGACCUAAAUUACAUCUCCACCAUUGUUCCUAAGAUGGCAUCUGAUUUUCUGUCUGGUAACAAGUCUAUCUCCUUCACUGGGUGUGGGAUUCAGAGUUUCUUCUUCUCGGCAUUAGGAGGUGCAGAAGCACUACUUUUGGCAUCUAUGGCCUAUGAUCGUUACAUUGCUAUUUGCUUUCCUCUUCACUAUCCCAUCCGCAUGAGCAAAAGAAUGUGUGUGCUGAUGAUAACAGGGUCUUGGAUCAUAGGCUCGAUCAAUGCUUGUGCUCACACUGUAUAUGUACUCCAUAUUCCUUAUUGCCAAUCCAGGGCCAUCAAUCAUUUCUUCUGUGAUGUCCCAGCAAUGGUGACUCUGGCCUGCAUGGACACCUGGGUCUAUGAGGGCACAGUGUUUUUGAGCACCACCAUCUUUCUCGUGUUUCCCUUCAUUGCUAUUUCAUGUUCCUAUGGCCGGGUUCUCCUUGCUGUCUACCACAUGAAAUCUGCAGAAGGGAGGAAGAAAGCCUACCUGACCUGCAGCACCCACCUCACUGUAGUAACUUUCUACUAUGCACCUUUUGUCUACACUUAUCUACGUCCAAGAUCCCUGCGAUCUCCAACAGAGGACAAGGUUCUGGCUGUCUUCUACACCACCCUCACUCCAAUGCUCAACCCCAUCAUCUAUAGCCUGAGGAACAAGGAGGUGAUGGGGGCCCUGACACGAGUGAGUCAGAGAAUCUGCUCUGGGAAAAUGUAGAAACAUUUUCUACCUAAGGUCUCAGGACUCAGAUACACAUCCAUCCAGCAGUGUAUAGUAAUUAAAAUAUUAUUUCAAUCCUAGAGUUCAGGAGCUAAAAGUAAUCAAGGUAAGAGAAAAAAAUCACUGAUUUCUGGACAAAAUUGUUUUACAUAUAUAUGUAUAUAUAACUCCAAACAACCUUUUUUCUUCAUGGCAUUGUUUCCAUAAAUUUUGAAAGCACCUACUUUUACUAAUAUGUUGUCAAUGAGAAUUUUUGUUUUUGGUCAUGCAGAAAUAGAAAUGAAAUUGGUCUAACUGAAGUUGGCACUCAGCAUAACAAUUUCCUUAUGGUCAGUUUAUUUUCCAGUAAUUUUAAAUUUACUUUUUUGUUUAUGUCUAAAACAAAACAAAAAAUAAGUCUCUUGACUUGGUGUAUCUAGUUGAAAGCUGUAAGAUGUUUUGUCUUUCUUAUCUUAGACACUUAACGUACCAAUUACUCAUUCUUUCAAUUUAGGGAACUCAUUACACAGUUUAGCAGAGAGCUCAUCAGGGAUUCUUAAGUCCUGAUACCACUCUGGAUGGCCUAUGACAAGAUUAUGUUCUUUAUAGGGGAAUGAAUCCCAGGAAAUGAUUUAACAUUAGGUAUAUUUUAGAUCAACAAAAGGACUGGAACAUGCCAGCAGUAAUAAAAAUGAUUACAUUUAGGUCUUUAACCUGUUUUGAGUUGAUUUGGAUAUAGUGUAAUGACUGGGAGUUUAUUUUCAUUUUUCUGCUUAAAAAUAUCCAGUUUUGCCAGCACCUUAUAUUGAAGACACUGUCUUUUUCCCAAUGAACAGUCUUGGGUCUGUUGUCAAAAAUCAGUUGCACAGAAAGGUUUUGCUUGUUCUCACUCCUAUGCGAGAGCUAGAAUUUUUAAAAACUGAACUAGUGGAAAUAGAGAAGAGACUGAUGGUCACCAGAGGGUGGGAAGGGUACAGGGGAGGGACGAUAAAGUGGGGAUGGCUAAUAGUUGCAAAAAUAUAAUUAGAUAGAAUGAAUAAGAGUAUUUGAUAGCACAAUAGAGUAACUAUAGUAAACAAUAAUUUAUUGUAGAAUUUAUUGUAUGUAUUAAAGAAUAACUGAAAGAGUGGAAUUGGAAUGUUCCCAACACAAAGAAAUAACCAUAUUUGAGGUGAUGGUUACCCCGAUUAACCCGAUUUGAUCAUUAUGCAUUGUAUGCCUUUAUCAAAGCAUCACAUACACUCCGCAAUUAUAUAUUACUAUUAUGUAUCCAUAGUAAUUAAAAUAAAAGAACCAGUUCACUGUAGAUAUAUGGAUUUAUUUCUGGGUUCUCUGUUCUGUUUCACUGUUCUAUGUGUCUGUUUUUAUGCCAGUACCAUUCUGUUUUGGUUAUUCCAUGUUUGUAGUAUAGUUUGAAGUUUGGUACUCAUGCCUCCAGUUUUUUCUUUUUAUUCUACAGUGCUUUGACUAUUUGGGUUCUUUAAUAGUUCCAUACAAAUCUUAAAUAAUGGUUUUUACUAUUUAUGUGCAGAAUGUCAUUGGUAUUUUGAUAGACAUUGCAUUGAAUCUGUAGUUUGGUUAUUUAAAUAAUAUUAAUUCUUCCAAUCCAUGAGCAUUGGAUUUCUUUCCAUUCAUUUGUAUUCCUCUUCAUUUUCUUUCACCAGUGAUUUGUACAAAUACAUUCUAGUGUUCUCUUCCAUGACUACCGUUAACGGUAAAGUAUUACAUAGUGCAAUGCUCUUUAAAUGUCAUUUCUAUUUCUAAGCCUGUGGAUAUUUGUUUUACCAUAUUGUAGCAGUUAAAAC